ACCCCGCGCAGCGCCGCCCGCCGUCGCCACCGCUCCCUCCCCGCCCGCCCCCGGCGGAGGCCGAGGGACUGGGCGGGGGGCUCCUGCAGGUAACCGCCUCCCGGGCCUGAGGGGCAGGGAGAGGGUUGGGCCUGAAGGACUGGGGCCGGGCCGGGGUGUCCGGCCUCGGGGGCUGGGAGCAGAGGUCCCGGCCGGACCCAACCUGGGAGUGCGGAGCCUCCUGGACUCCGAGUCAGGGCUUGGGGUGCUGAGGGGAGUGUUGCUGCCCGGCCCGACCCAAGAGUGCGGGCAGGGGCCCGGGCCAGGCCUGGCAUCAGAGGGCUAAGGUGUCUUGGGCCGGCCCGGGGUUCCGGCGGGGCUUGGGUGCCGGUGCUGGCCCGAGGGUGCGGAGGGAAGGUCUACCUGCUGGUCGCGCGAGGCCUUGGGUGCAAAGGCGGCGGGUGUGAGCGGGCGGCGUCCGGGAGUCAGCGCCGCCUGCUUCGGGGCCCCUGGCAGCCCCGGGGGCACCGGCCGCGCUCGCCUCUUGGCUACGGGCUGGAGGCGAGGCCAGCGGGGCUGGGCCGGGAUGUGGGCGGGAGGGCGCCGCGCUGGGGCGCCCAGGAGAGCAGGGGCCCGUUUACUGCCAUGUGAACACCUGAAGCCAUGUGGACGCGGCUGCUUCUCGCCUGUUGGGGGCGGAGGGCAGGUACCGGCGGGUUGGGCGCAAGGUCCCGGCGCAGGACACACUUCCUGUGUGGGGCGGCCUCUCCUCCCGCGCCGCGGGGAACAGGGCGGGGUGUGCAAGCCGGGGUCUCUGGGCGAGGGAGCGCUCGUUUGGGGACCUGAGGCUUUCGUCCCUUUUUCGGGGGAAAGUGGUGGUUUGAAGGAGCGUGGCCAAUCGGGCCGAUCCCUCUCAGGCUACGGCGGGAGGUGCACUGUCCUCUGGACGCCGGAAUGGGAGUGGAAUUUAGUGAGUUGGGGGGCGGUGCCGAGGAGCGGCCGUCUUCCUCUGCUUGUGGGUGGGAUUAUUGUCUGUUUUUGUGGUUGCGGAUACCAAUACGGUCUGCUGGUCUGUAUUCAAUCCUUUAGUUUGACCUUAGGGGUCAGGUCAAAAUUAGGAUUUCCCCCUUUUCCUUUUUGCUUUUUUUUCCUCGAAGAUUAGAUGUCUCUGGUAACUGCUGUAAAAUGGAUGGAAUUUUCGAGCUAUUAUCUAACAGGCUGAUCUUUGAAUGAUAAUUGGACCCUUAUGUUAACAGCCUCAGUGAAGAGUGAAGAGUUUUAUACAGCAUCUUCCGUGGGGUGGCAGUUAGGUGGAUGGGGAAGCUACACUGAAUUCCGACCUGGGAGACCAGGAAUCUGCUUACAGCUUUGACGCCAAAUAAACUGCAGCCCAGGGCAAGUUACUUUCCCUGGUAAUUUUCUCAUCUGUUAAGUGAGGACUCCCGGGUCAGACGGUACAGGGGUUUGUGGUUUUGCUUUUUUAUCUCUCAUUUUGUGCUCUGUUUUAGCCAUAGGCAACUUUUCUGAGAAAUGCAGACUGUACCUUAGCUGGCUUUUAAAAGCCUGUCUUUAAGCUUCCAGCCUCUGCCUUCAACAGAGCAUAAAAGUUGGUCAGGGUACGCUCUUUUUUGAAAUCCCACUUGCUGUUCUGUGCUUCAGAUCAGAAAGUGUAUUAUUCUGACCUAGGUGGAAUGCACCUUAACAUAUUUUUUGUCUUUGUGAAAGAAGUUAUCAGAAAAUGUUUCAGAGAAUAUUUGUCUACUUGGAAAAUGUGUGGAUAACAUGUGAUUGGGUCUGUGUAUGUUGGCUCAGAGGAGUUCCAAGAUCUUUCUACGCAGGGGAUUUUGGAGGAUCCAGAUUUUAUUAAAGUUCUUCAAAGGACAUUUGACAUUUGGCUAACUGUUGAAAUUUCCAGCCAGUUUCAGCAUUCUCAGAGUAGGGGGAUGAAGUAGAAUGCCAUAACAUCUCCUGUGAAAUGGUAUGCUAGUGGAAUUAACUGUCACCUCAGGGUGCACUGAUUAUCUGCAUCCCCAACUUUCUCCUUACUGGUAGCCAGUGCUCCGCAGAUGCUGAAGAACCGCAAUUAGUUUCACUGAUUUUAUGGUGUGUGAAGGCCUUAGGCUGUGCUUUUGACUGGAGGGCUGUUGGCCUGCUGCUGUGCUGCUGAACAGUAUGCAGUCCUUUCGGGAGCAAAGCAGUUACCACGGAAACCAGCAAAGCUACCCACAGGAGGUACACGGCUCAUCCCGGCUAGAAGAGUUCAGCCCUCGUCAGGCCCAGAUGUUCCAGAAUUUUGGAGGUACAGGUGGCAGUAGUGGCAGCAGUGGCAGUGGCAGUGGUGGUGGACGACGAGGAGCAGCAGCUGCUGCGGCAGCGAUGGCUAGCGAGACCUCUGGCCAUCAAGGUUACCAGGGUUUCAGGAAAGAGGCUGGAGAUUUUUACUACAUGGCAGGCAACAAAGACCCCGUGACUACAGGAACCCCACAGCCUCCUCAGCGAAGGCCUUCUGGGCCUGUGCAGAGCUAUGGACCCCCCCAGGGGAGCAGCUUUGGCAAUCAGUAUGGGAGUGAGGGUCAUGUGGGCCAGUUUCAAGCACAGCACUCUGGCCUUGGCGGUGUGUCACAUUAUCAGCAGGAUUACACUGGGCCUUUCUCUCCAGGGAGUGCUCAGUACCAACAGCAGGCUUCCAGCCAGCAGCAGCAGCAGCAAGUCCAGCAGUUGAGACAACAGCUUUACCAGUCCCAUCAGCCCCUGCCACAGGCCACUGGCCAACCAGCAUCCAGCUCAUCCCAUCUACAGCCAAUGCAGCGGCCCUCAACUCUGCCAUCCUCUGCUGCUGGUUACCAGUUAAGAGUGGGUCAGUUUGGCCAACACUAUCAGUCUUCUGCUUCCUCCUCCUCCUCCUCCUCCUUCCCUUCACCACAGCGUUUUAGCCAGUCUGGACAGAGCUAUGAUGGCAGUUACAAUGUGAAUGCUGGAUCUCAGUAUGAAGGACACAAUGUGGGUUCUAAUGCACAGGCUUAUGGAACACAAUCCAAUUACAGCUAUCAGCCUCAAUCUAUGAAGAAUUUUGAACAGGCAAAGAUUCCACAAGGGACCCAACAGGGGCAGCAGCAGCAGCAACCGCAGCAACAACAACACCCUUCUCAGCAUGUGAUGCAGUAUACUAACGCUGCCACCAAGCUGCCCCUGCAAAGCCAAGUGGGGCAGUACAACCAGCCUGAGGUUCCUGUGAGGUCCCCCAUGCAGUUUCACCAGAACUUCAGCCCCAUUUCUAACCCUUCUCCAGCUGCCUCUGUGGUUCAGUCUCCAAGCUGUAGUUCUACCCCAUCUCCUCUCAUGCAGACUGGGGAGAAUCUCCAGUGUGGGCAAGGCAGUGUGCCUAUGGGUUCCAGAAACAGAAUUUUACAGUUAAUGCCUCAACUCAGUCCAACCCCAUCAAUGAUGCCCAGUCCUAAUUCUCAUGCUGCAGGCUUCAAAGGGUUUGGACUAGAAGGGGUACCAGAAAAGCGACUGACAGAUCCUGGGUUGAGUAGUUUGAGUGCUCUGAGUACUCAAGUGGCCAAUCUUCCUAACACUGUCCAGCACAUGUUACUUUCUGAUGCCCUGACUCCUCAGAAGAAGACCUCCAAGAGGCCCUCAUCUUCCAAGAAAGCAGAUAGCUGCACAAAUUCUGAAGGCUCCUCACAACCUGAAGAACAGCUGAAGUCCCCUAUGGCAGAGUCAUUAGAUGGAGGCUGCUCCAGCAGUUCAGAGGAUCAAGGCGAGAGAGUGCGGCAACUAAGUGGCCAGAGCACCAGCUCUGACACCACCUACAAGGGUGGAGCCUCUGAGAAAGCUGGCUCCUCACCGGCACAAGGUGCUCAGAAUGAACCCCCCAGACUCAAUGCUAGUCCUGCCGCAAGAGAAGAGGCCACCUCACCAGGCGCUAAGGACAUGCCAUUGUCAUCCGACGGGAACCCAAAGGUUAAUGAGAAGACUGUUGGGGUGAUUGUCUCCCGGGAAGCCAUGACAGGUCGGGUAGAAAAGCCUGGUGGACAAGAUAAAGGCUCCCAAGAGGAUGAUCCUGCAGCCACUCAAAGGCCACCUAGCAAUGGUGGGGCAAAGGAAACCAGUCAUGCAUCACUUCCCCAGCCAGAGCCUCCAGGAGGAGGAGGGAGCAAAGGAAACAAGAAUGGCGAUAACAACUCCAACCAUAAUGGAGAAGGAAAUGGCCAGAGUGGCCACUCUGCAGCGGGCCCUGGUUUUACGAGCAGAACUGAGCCUAGCAAAUCUCCUGGAAGUCUGCGCUAUAGUUACAAAGAUAGUUUCGGGUCAGCCGUGCCACGAAAUGUCAGUGGCUUUCCUCAGUAUCCUACAGGGCAAGAAAAGGGAGAUUUCACUGGCCAUGGGGAACGAAAGGGUAGAAAUGAAAAAUUCCCAAGCCUCCUGCAGGAAGUGCUUCAGGGUUACCACCACCACCCUGACAGGAGAUAUUCUAGGAGUACUCAAGAGCAUCAGGGGAUGGCUGGUAGCCUAGAAGGAACCACAAGGCCCAAUGUCUUGGUUAGUCAAACCAAUGAAUUAGCUAGCAGGGGCCUUCUGAACAAAAGCAUUGGGUCUCUAUUAGAAAAUCCCCACUGGGGCCCCUGGGAAAGGAAAUCAAGCAGCACAGCUCCUGAAAUGAAACAGAUCAAUUUGACUGACUAUCCAAUUCCCAGAAAGUUUGAAAUAGAGCCUCAGUCAUCAGCACAUGAGCCUGGGGGUUCCCUCUCUGAAAGAAGAUCAGUGAUCUGUGAUAUUUCUCCACUAAGACAGAUUGUCAGGGACCCAGGGGCUCACUCACUGGGACACAUGAGUGCCGACACCAGAAUUGGGAGGAAUGACCGUCUCAAUCCAACUUUAAGUCAGUCGGUCAUUCUUCCUGGUGGUUUGGUGUCCAUGGAAACCAAGCUGAAAUCCCAGAGCGGGCAGAUAAAAGAGGAAGACUUUGAACAGUCUAAAUCUCAAGCUAGUUUCAACAACAAGAAAUCUGGAGACCACUGCCAUCCUCCUAGCAUCAAGCAUGAGUCUUACCGCGGCAAUGCCAGCCCUGGAGCAGCAACCCAUGAUUCCCUUUCAGACUAUGGCCCGCAAGACAGCAGACCCACGCCAAUGCGGCGGGUCCCUGGCAGAGUUGGUGGUCGGGAGGGCAUGAGGGGUCGGUCCCCUUCUCAAUAUCAUGACUUUGCAGAAAAAUUGAAAAUGUCUCCUGGGCGGAGCAGAGGCCCAGGGGGAGACCCUCAUCACAUGAAUCCACACAUGACCUUUUCAGAGAGGGCUAACCGGAGUUCUUUACACACUCCCUUUUCUCCCAACUCAGAAACCCUGGCCUCUGCUUAUCAUGCAAAUACUCGGGCUCAUGCUUAUGGGGACCCUAACGCAGGUUUGAAUUCUCAGCUGCAUUAUAAGAGACAGAUGUACCAACAGCAACCAGAGGAGUAUAAAGACUGGAGCAGCGGUUCUGCUCAGGGAGUAAUUGCUGCAGCACAGCACAGGCAGGAGGGGCCACGGAAGAGUCCAAGGCAGCAGCAGUUUCUUGACAGAGUACGGAGCCCUCUGAAAAAUGACAAAGAUGGUAUGAUGUAUGGCCCACCAGUGGGGACUUACCAUGACCCCAGUGCCCAGGAGGCUGGGCGCUGCCUAAUGUCUAGUGAUGGUCUGCCUAACAAGGGCAUGGAAUUAAAGCAUGGCUCCCAGAAGUUACAAGAAUCCUGUUGGGAUCUUUCUCGGCAAACUUCUCCAGCCAAAAGCAGCGGUCCUCCAGGAAUGUCCAGUCAAAAAAGGUAUGGGCCGCCCCAUGAGACUGAUGGACAUGGACUAGCUGAGGCUACACAGUCAUCCAAACCUGGUAGUGUUAUGCUGAGACUUCCAGGCCAGGAGGAUCAUUCUUCUCAAAACCCCUUAAUCAUGAGGAGGCGUGUUCGUUCUUUUAUCUCUCCCAUUCCCAGUAAGAGACAGUCACAAGAUGUAAAGAACAGUAGCACUGAAGAUAAAGGUCGCCUCCUUCACUCAUCAAAAGAAGGCGCUGAUAAAGCAUUCAAUUCCUAUGCCCAUCUUUCUCACAGUCAGGAUAUCAAGUCUAUCCCUAAGAGAGAUUCCUCCAAGGACCUUCCAAGUCCAGAUAGUAGAAACUGCCCUGCUGUUACCCUCACAAGCCCUGCUAAGACCAAAAUACUGCCCCCACGGAAAGGACGGGGAUUGAAAUUGGAAGCUAUAGUUCAGAAGAUUACAUCCCCAAAUAUUAGGAGGAGCGCAUCUUCGAACAGUGCGGAGGCUGGGGGAGACACGGUUACGCUUGAUGAUAUACUGUCUUUGAAGAGUGGUCCUCCUGAAGGUGGGAGUGUUGCUGUUCAGGAUGCUGACAUAGAGAAGAGAAAAGGUGAGGUGGCUUCGGACCUAGUCAGUCCAGCAAACCAGGAGUUGCACGUAGAGAAACCUCUUCCAAGGUCUUCAGAAGAGUGGCGUGGCAGCGUGGAUGACAAAGUGAAGACAGAGACACAUGCAGAAACAGUUACUGCCGGAAAGGAACCCCCUGGUGCCAUGACAUCCACAACCUCACAGAAGCCUGGUAGUAACCAAGGGAGACCAGAUGGUUCCCUGGGUGGAACAGCACCUUUAAUCUUUCCAGACUCAAAGAAUGUACCUCCAGUGGGCAUAUUGGCCCCUGAGGCAAACCCCAAGGCUGAAGAGAAGGAGAACGAUACAGUGACGAUUUCACCGAAGCAAGAGGGUUUCCCUCCAAAGGGAUAUUUCCCAUCAGGAAAGAAGAAGGGGAGACCCAUUGGUAGUGUGAAUAAGCAAAAGAAACAGCAGCAGCCACCGCCUCCACCCCCUCAGCCCCCACAGAUACCAGAAGGUUCUGCAGAUGGAGAGCCAAAGCCAAAAAAACAGAGGCAAAGGAGGGAGAGAAGGAAGCCUGGGGCCCAGCCGAGGAAGCGAAAAACCAAACAAGCAGUUCCCAUUGUGGAACCCCAAGAACCUGAGAUCAAACUAAAAUAUGCCACCCAGCCACUGGAUAAAACUGAUGCCAAGAACAAGUCUUUUUACCCUUACAUCCAUGUAGUAAAUAAGUGUGAACUUGGAGCCGUUUGUACAAUCAUCAAUGCUGAGGAAGAAGAACAGACCAAAUUAGUGAGGGGCAGGAAGGGUCAGAGGUCACUGACCCCUCCACCUAGCAGCACUGAAAGCAAGGCGCUCCCGGCCUCGUCCUUUAUGCUGCAGGGACCUGUUGUGACAGAGUCUUCGGUUAUGGGGCACCUGGUUUGCUGUCUGUGUGGCAAGUGGGCCAGUUACCGGAACAUGGGUGACCUCUUUGGACCUUUUUAUCCCCAAGAUUAUGCAGCCACUCUCCCGAAGAAUCCACCUCCUAAGAGGGCCACAGAAAUGCAGAGCAAAGUUAAGGUACGGCACAAAAGUGCUUCUAAUGGCUCCAAGACGGACACUGAGGAGGAGGAAGAGCAGCAGCAGCAGCAGAAGGAGCAGAGAAGCCUGGCCGCACACCCCAGGUUUAAGCGGCGCCACCGCUCGGAAGACUGUGGUGGAGGCCCUCGGUCCCUGUCCAGGGGGCUCCCUUGUAAAAAAGCAGCCACUGAGGGCAGCAGUGAAAAGACUGUUUUGGACUCGAAGCCCUCCGUGCCCACCACUUCAGAAGGUGGCCCUGAGCUGGAGUUACAAAUCCCUGAACUACCUCUUGACAGCAAUGAAUUUUGGGUCCAUGAGGGUUGUAUUCUCUGGGCCAAUGGAAUCUACCUGGUUUGUGGCAGGCUCUAUGGCCUGCAGGAAGCGCUGGAAAUAGCCAGAGAGAUGAAAUGUUCCCACUGCCAGGAGGCAGGCGCCACCUUGGGCUGCUACAACAAAGGCUGCUCCUUCCGAUACCAUUACCCGUGUGCCAUUGAUGCAGAUUGUUUGCUACAUGAGGAGAACUUCUCGGUGAGGUGCCCUAAGCACAAGCCUCCCCUUCCGUGCCCUCUCCCCCCCUUGCAGAACAAGACCGCGAAAGGCAGCCUCAGCACAGAGCAGUCGGAGCGGGGGUGAGGGGGGCAGUGUGCUCGUGGGAAUGGAAAGGACAGCAAGCACAGGUGAGACUGUGGAGAUGAGAAGGUGGUGGACACUCGUGAUGGAAUGGAAAUCGUCCUACCGUGCAGCCACACCCUGCCCUGCCCCGCCCCGCCCCGCCCGCGUGCCUGCCCAUGCCAGCACUUCCUUAAGUUCUCACAUCACACUCAAACCAGUGACACCACAGGAAAGAAAGACCCAAGACGUUGGAAUGGCUGUUUCCAUGGACACAAUCUCCAUAGUGACAAUGUGGGGGGAGGGGGGAGGGGUGGGAUGAUGGGGAAAGGGUGGGGGGAAUUAAAAGGGAGGGAUAAAUAUAUAUAUAUAAAUCUAUUUUUAGUCUGGAAAGACUUUGUUUAAAUGAAAGGUGCGCUAUCCCUUUUGAUUCUGUUUUAAAAUUAUCUCGUUAAAGAUCUCCAAAUUUGUUCCGAUGACAAGUGAAAUUUAAAUGUGAGAUUGAACUGAACAAACCCUCAUCUCAUGAAGGACGGGGUGUGUGUGUGGCGUUGAUCUUUAGCCUGUCUCACACCAGUUCAGAAAACACUAGACCCAGGAUUGAAAAAGCAAACCACAGCAGAACCAUCCUUUUGUCAUUAAUUUGUCUCAAAGUGGGAAGGUUUUGGGGGAGGGGGAAAUACAGGGAUGGUCCAUGUUUUCAAGAGUAGGGGAAUGAUGUUUAAACACAAAAAUAAAUUUUUUUUCAUUUCCAGAAACACUAUUUAUUUAUGGUUUUUUUUUUUUAAUUUUUUCUUUUUGGGGGUGAAAUUGGCAGAUGCCUGAGGUCAUAGCUGUGUCCUGGGUCACUGUGGCUGGUGAGGACCUCAAGGACCCCAUCAAGUGUACACAGCAGCAGCAAAAUCAAGGGAUGACCCUCCUCUGGGGCCCCCUGUCCUCAGCACAUUCCAGGCAGCUGUGCCCUGACCCACAGGGACCCGUGGGGAUGGGAGGAGGUCCAGGCCUGUGUUGCCAGAGCUGGCAGUGUGAGCUGUAGGCAGGGACGGGGAGGGACUGUCGCUGUGAUCAGAGUGGGUUAAGCUGACCAGGAACACCCAUUUAACCCCUUUUUCUUUUUGCUUUCAUUUUUAUAAAGGAAAAGAGGACCUGUCAGAUAGGCAGCCCCAUGCUACGUGAUUCUUUAUGUUGUGUUGUUUUGUUUUGUAAAUUGUAUAAUUUUUAAAUAUCUGAGUUUUAAAAAAAGAAAAAAGUACAAAAAAAUCUUGUUAUGGCCUUAAGAAGGGGUUAGUGCAUCUUUCAGGGGUCACUCUGCCAUGGGGAUAAAAUAGCUGUUUCACAAACAGUUUUAUUUAAAAAAACAAAAAACAAAAAAAAUCAAAAAAUCAAAAAAAUAAUAAACUUCAUUUUAACCUUG